GUACACUUGAACAUGGUUAAAAUGGUAAACUGUAUGUUAUUUAUAUUUAAUCCAAUUUUCAAAAGAUAAUUAGCUCAAGAAGACUUGUUACCAGGUGGGCAAGAGAGAUUGCUUAUAGUGCUUUGUGACUGUAGACACUAAAAACAAUUUGUCUUUCUAUUGAAACCCAAUGAUUAGAAACAUCUGAUGCUAAGGAGUAAUCUUUCCUACUCUUUAUUUUUGUACUUGGUGCCUCAGCUGUUAAGAGUCAAAUUGUAUUAGUUCAGCCCUGUAGCUGCACUUCAAAUGGUCACUUAAAAGGAAUUGCCUUCUAAGAGGUACAUAUUUAGGAGAUGCAGAUGUGUUGUGAGCUUAUUUUUCUUGGGUUGGUUUGUAAGCUGUAAAUGUCGUGUAACCUUGACAGAGCUAUUUUGAGGACCAGCAAAACAAGCCGUGCUAACAUGUCUUCCAAGUAAAGGUGUGUUGGCAUCAUCUGCAAAUUACAAAUAGCUUUCAAACCUAUAAUUCUACCCCAUUUGUCCUGUGGGUCCUCAUACUCAUUAUGUCUAAAGUGAACACCCUUGCCCAUCUUUUGUUUCCUCUGUGUUAGGGGGGCACACAAUCCAUCUAGUCGUGCACAGUUGAAACUCUGGGAUUGUCUUUGGCUCAUCCUCUCUUAUGUGUAUUUUGUGACACUUAUUACAAUAGUAAUUACAUAACUAUUUAUAGUGUUGUAACUCCACAAGAGCAGGGCUGUGACUGAAUUAUUUACUGAGGUAUCUACAUAAUAGCUGCUCAGUAAACCACUGUCCUAAUUGAGAUCCUCUUCAUCUUUUACCUAACCCAGGAUUUCUUUAACUUUACUAGCAUGUUGAGAGAAUUCUUACCGACCUUCUAGUGAAUGAGCCUACUAACAGAUUGUUUUUCUAGGGAAAAACAGAUUUCAUUGUAGGGAAUGAGCUACUAACAGAUUGUUUUUCCCCAGGCUUAAUUCUGAUCUUAUUCUGCUCUGAGUGGCUUCUCAUUUCGUUUUCAUUCAGCAGGGUGCUCAGCAGGUAUGUCAGCACCUUCCAUGUGCCAAGUACUGUUCUAGGUGCUGAGGGUGCAGCAGUGAGCAGAGUAGGCCAAGCCUUUUUGAGUAUGAGCUUACAUCCUAGUGGAGUAGCAGACAAUAAACAGAUGGAAGAUGUCCAGUGGUGACCAGUGCCAUGAAGAAAAGUAAAGCAGGAGCCAGCCUCUCUUAAUAGAGAUCUAAAUGAAGUGAGGGAGCAAUCCAUGAGGAUAUCUGAAGGCAGAGGGAACAGUAAGCACGGAGCCCUGAGGCAGGAGCACACUUGGUGUUUUGGGGAAACAGCAAGAAGCCAGAAUGAUAAGGGCAGAGUGACCAAGGAGAAAAGUGGAAGGACACGAGGUCAGAGAAGUAGCCACCCAGCCCAGCACAGUUCCUUGCAUGUGUAUGGUAUGGCUCAGUAAAUACGUUGUGAAUGAAUGAAUGAAACCAAUCAAUAAUUAUGUAUUUAUGAAUAAAAAAUCAGGGCAGGGUGUUAGAGGUAUACCUAAGGUAAUAGAAAGUUAGGAUGCAUAUUCCAUGGUUCAUGAAGACAGCACUGCGUUUUGCUUGCACUUUCCCCUUCGGUUUAGGAGAGAUGAUGAUAAUGGCCGGAGCCAGAAGACUAAUUCUGACUUGUUCUUGAAGGAAAUUCUGUUCUGCACACAGUGACAAUCAGAGGUUAGAAACUUGUCAGCGGAGCCGUGAGUCGAGCAGAGCUGCUCAGCUCUUGGUGGUUGUAAAACGUGCCUCUACCUCAUGUUUGAGAAAGCUUGUGUUUUCCGUGUAUAUGGCUUAGCAUUUUAAGUAAUCACGAUAUCUGAGGGGUAAUGGGAAUGCAGGAGCAGCAGGUGGUGGCUAGUUUUCUGUAGGAUUUAGGAAAGGACUGCUGAUUUAACUGAAUCUCUGAUUAUUCUAAGCUGCUCAUAGAAAUCCACCAGUCACUGCUGUCUCAGACGUCAGAGGGAGAAGCUUAAGCAUGUUCUGUUGUUGACAGCCAUUCUGGUUGACUUCUCUAAGACUGCCAGCUGUAUUCUUGAUAUUCAGAGUCCUGCAGAUGUGGCCCCUCUCUGCUAUUCUACCCUGCUUUCCCACAGUGUCCUCUUGCAUCAGCUGGCCAUCUCUCCAUGACUGUGUUCCCCCUCCUCUGGGCCUUUGCUCUAGUGUUCCUUUGGCUUGGAGUAUCUGCUCACAUCUGCCAAGCAGAGCCGUAUCCAUGCUUCAAGCUUUCUUCCAUAUUUUCUUCCUUUGCUUUCUUUCCUUUUUCUUUCUUCCCUUGCUUUCCCUUUCCCUUUCUCUUUCUCCUCUUUUCUUUUUUCUUUCUUCAGGGUCUUGCUCUUGCCCAGGCUGGUGCAGUGGUGCAAUCAUAGUUCAUUGUAACCUCGAAUUCCUGGGCUCAAGUGAUCUUCCCACCUCAGCUUUCUGAGUAGCUGGAACUACAGGUGUGUUGCCACCACACUCAGUUAAUUUAAAAAAAAAUUUUUUUUUUUUGGUAGAUACAGGGUCUUGCUUUGUUGCCCAGGCUGGUCUCGAACUCCUGGCCUCAGGCAAUCCUCCCACCUCGGCCUCACAAAGUGCUGUGUAGCCACUGUGCCCGGCCCCUUCAAAGUUUUCUUUUCUCAAAGGGACCCAUGCCCUCUUUCUUGUGCUCUGUCCUAUCACAGUGGGGGGUUGUGUGAAGUCCCAUCUCUCUGAAGACAGUCUUCUCAUAUCCCUCCAGGUGUAGUUCAUCUCCCCCUCUUCCACUGCACCUUAACCCCUCAUUACUUAGUGUUGUCAUUGGACUAAUAGCGUCAGCAUCACCUGGGUGGGGGCCUGUUCGAAGUGCAGAAUUUCAGGUCCCGCCCCAGACCUACUGAACUAGAAUCUGGUGCUUCUUACAUCCUGUGCACAUUAAAGUUUGAGAAGCAUUGCCGCCACACAUUGGUCCUACUCCCCUUACUGGUCUGAGCAGGAUGUAGAUGGUUCGAGUGUUUUUGUUCCCCUCUAGAUGUUGAACUCCUGAAUCGUGAGCCAUCUCUUACCUAGUAUAGUUCUUAGCAUGUUUCAAGCACUUAAAAGUAUUUACUGAAUUACCUUAACUAACCCCUGACCUUAUGUUUGAGAUGCUUCUUCAGUCAACAUACUAUAUAAGUGCAUUUACCUGUGCUUGGUGCUUGUAGGUGCAUGAGACACCCUGCUGUGAAUGGGAGUCAGCCUCUGUCUUUGGCAUUUAUAGAUGAGUGGGGAAGAUAGAUUAUGCAUCAAUUAUUAAUAAUUAUGAGAAAAGGCAGAGUCUGAUAAAUUCUGUAACUGCAUAGGCAUCACCAGAGGCCUAAGGGAACAUCAAAGGAGUAGCUGAUAUUUACAGUUCUGAGGGUUUGUGACUGUUGCAUGGAAAGGAUGGUAUUUAGUUGGUACAUUGCAAGAUGAAUAGGACUUUGACAGACAGGCACAGUGGAAAGAGGCAUUCCAGGCCAGGGGAGAGUGUUCAGAGGCCCAGGCAUGAAAGUACACCUACAGUGUUUCUUAAAUAAGUAAGACAUAGAGGAGCAAGGUGGAAGGUGGGAUUGGAGAGGUCGAUUGAGUACAGACUGUGUACUCCUUAAAUUUUCAUGGUGAGGAGUCUAGACUGCUAAGAAACACCUGCAAAUCAGUUGAAGUUGGUAUAGUUACAUGUUCAGUGGUUCCUGAGGACUCUGCCCACUUCUCUCCCUUCCUCUGCUCCCAUUCUACCUUGCUGGAUCUGAGUAGUAGGAAGUGGGGGGAGGGUUUAGAAGAAGUGGGAAGCAGCCUGAAUGUUUUAGCCAGCUGUUCAUAUGGGACUGGAGCCCCAAGUCCUUUUUUAGUGUCAGCUGGUCAGCUACUUCCUUCCUCACCCCCUUCCUGUGUCACUACCCAGUGGGGCACUCUAAAGCAGAGAGACCAAAACUCCAUCACAGAGUGUUCAAAGAGUGUGCUCUAAAAUGCUAUCGAAAACUGCAGACUGAGCCCAGUAUGUUUUAUUAUACUUGCCAUCAGUUUCUUAACCCCAAGAGUUUAUGAGGACUCAUCAUUUCUGCUUGUGGUAGUACUAUAUGAACCUGUGUCUCUCUGUCCGUAUUCUAGGCUGGCAGUCAGGCCAUCAGCAUUGAAGGUGAAAGAAUCCCCCUGACUUCCAUUUCCUUAUAUGCCAUCUUGUUAGAAACCCACAAAGUAGCUAGUGUGGUCUGUUUAUUUCUUCAGGACUGGGAAUGCACUGUUACCCUGGGAGUCAGGCCCUCCACAAAUUGACCCUAAGCCUCACCAUCUUUUUCUUGAGCUUUUUACUUCAGCCAACUGAAUUUUCAGAUGAGAUGAGAAGGUCAUGCUUUUCCACCUUUGAGCUCCCACUUUGACCAGCUCUGCCAGUCCUGAGCCAGAAGGUCAACAGUUAAAAAGAAGAGAUUGGGGACCACAAAUUCAGUGCCCACCGGAUUGUCUUAGCAGCCUCGAUCCCGUAUUUCCAUGCUAUGUUUACAAAUGACAUGAUGGAGUGCAAGCAGGAUGAGAUUGUAAUGCAAGGAAUGGACCCAAGUGCCCUGGAGGCUCUGAUCAACUUUGCCUACAACGGCAACCUUGCCAUUGACCAGCAAAAUGUCCAGUCAUUGCUGAUGGGGGCGAGCUUCCUGCAGCUGCAGAGCAUCAAAGACGCCUGCUGCACAUUCCUUCGAGAACGGCUUCACCCAAAAAACUGCCUGGGUGUGCGCCAGUUUGCUGAGACAAUGAUGUGUGCUGUGCUGUACGACGCUGCCAACAGCUUCAUCCACCAGCACUUUGUGGAGGUGUCCAUGUCAGAAGAGUUCCUGGCCCUGCCCUUGGAAGACGUGCUUGAGCUGGUGUCUCGGGAUGAGCUGAAUGUCAAAUCUGAGGAGCAGGUCUUUGAAGCUGCAUUGGCCUGGGUCAGAUACGACCGGGAGCAGAGGGGUCCCUACCUGCCUGAGCUGCUGUCCAAUAUCCGCCUGCCCCUCUGUCGGCCCCAGUUCCUUUCAGACAGAGUACAGCAGGAUGACCUGGUGCGUUGCUGCCACAAAUGCAGGGACCUGGUAGACGAAGCAAAGGACUACCACCUCAUGCCAGAGCGCCGGCCCCACCUGCCAGCUUUCAGAACCCGGCCACGCUGCUGCACAUCCAUCGCUGGACUUAUCUACGCUGUAGGGGGCCUCAACUCAGCAGCAAAUUUUUAUGCAGGUGAUUCCCUGAAUGUGGUGGAAGUGUUCGACCCCAUUGCCAAUUGCUGGGAGAGAUGCCGUCCCAUGACAACAGCCCGCAGCCGCGUUGGCGUGGCUGUGGUGAACGGGCUUCUCUAUGCCAUCGGAGGAUAUGACGGCCAGCUACGGCUGAGCACUGUGGAGGCCUACAACCCGGAGACAGACACAUGGACCAGAGUGGGGAGCAUGAAUAGCAAGAGAAGCUCUGUCUGUUUCAGUGCCAUGGGGACAGUCGUGCUGGAUGGGCAGAUCUACGUCUGUGGGGGCUACGAUGGCAACUCUUCCCUCAGCUCCGUGGAGACCUACUCACCUGAGACGGACAAAUGGACAGUGGUGACCUCGAUGAGCUCGAAUCGCAGUGCUGCUGGGGUUACAGUCUUUGAGGGCAGGAUAUAUGUGUCAGGCGGCCAUGAUGGUUUGCAGAUCUUCAGCAGUGUGGAACACUACAACCACCACACAGCCACCUGGCACCCUGCAGCUGGCAUGCUCAACAAGCGCUGCCGGCACGGAGCCGCCUCCCUGGGGAGCAAGAUGUUUGUCUGCGGGGGCUACGAUGGCUCUGGCUUCCUCAGCAUUGCCGAGAUGUACAGCUCUGUGGCAGACCAGUGGUGCCUGAUUGUCCCCAUGCACACGCGCAGGAGCCGGGUCUCCCUGGUGGCCAGCUGUGGGCGCCUCUACGCUGUUGGGGGCUACGACGGACAGUCAAACCUAAGCUCAGUGGAGAUGUAUGACCCAGAGACAGACUGCUGGACAUUCAUGGCCCCCAUGGCGUGCCAUGAGGGAGGGGUCGGUGUGGGCUGCAUCCCUCUCCUCACCAUCUAAGGCAGAGGAUGGGAUGUGGUGGGGCAGGGAUCUGGUACAGACAUAGGCGCUUCCUUCCAGGAACAGUCCCUCAGGAGAGGCAGUGGACCAGAAGAGAUGGCGAAACGUGAGCUCGCCGGAGGUACAGUUUUUCCAGGUGCUUAAGCCCUCCCCCACUGUGCCACCCUUGUGACCUUCAGGCUUGGGUCAUCAAGAUGCACAGCAUGGAACACAAGCUCCUCUGGAUCCUGCAGCUGGUGACAUGGAACUGUUUUCUGGUCCACAUGAACACAGGCUCCAUCCAGGCCCAGCUCCUACCCACCGCCUCUCUGUGGGCCAGCUGUUCACAGAAGGCCUUCCAUCUGAUGCUCCCCAUCGCCUGCUUGCUCUCCAGCCGAGUCUGGCCAAUUUGCCAUGGGGAGGCUGCAGUGUCCAAGCCUGCUGGAAACUGGGAUGUAGCUGGGGACGAAAGGACAGACCCAAGCGUUCUCCCUGCCUGAGAUGGUGUGGCCACAGCAGUGGAAGGCUGCACACAGGCACAUUCCUUCUUCCACAGUGGGGCACCAAGGAUUCUGUCCUCAUUGCUGGGUAAGCAGGGAGAAGAGAAGUUUUCCCCAUGUCUAAUUUUGGGAUUUCAGUGAGGCCUUUUGAUCUGUCCAGGAGAACAGAAGGGAAAAAAAGAUACUUGAAAGAAACUGAAGGAAAUUUAAACAAAGAAACACUUGAAAGAAACUGGAAAGAAAAAUAAUUUUUUUAUGUGAACAAAUUUUGCAAGAAGAAAAAAGCAUAAAAGACACUAACGGCAAAUCUAUGUUUAAAUGGAAAAUCGUCUAACUGGAGAAGGGCGGUAUCCACCCCACAUUCGGAUCCCAGGGUCCUGAGGCCUCGCAUUGAGCUGGGGGUUCCCUCUGAGCCCCAGUGUGUGUGGAAUCAGUGCACUCUUGACUGGGCCUGUAGUAAGGUGCUCAUGGGGUUUGUCUUCUCACCCACCAUCAGAGGACUUUUAAAAUCAUAGGCGUAGAGAGUUAGGCUAUCUGCUGAAUUACUGCCACUCUUCUUGGUGGGGGCUCCUAGCUGUGGCUGGGGGCUCCAGGCGCCCCUGUGAUUACCUCCUACUGCCACCAUGGCGCUCAUUCAGAUUCCCCACUCUCACUAACAUUGCUUCCUUUUUUGACCAGCAGGAAACAGCAGGUCUGGCCAGAUUCUCACUUGCCCAUCAAUCUCGUUCUUGGAUGAUUUCCCUCAUUGUGAUGCUUCUGGGGCACGUUGACCAUAUGCACCUCUAGAACCUAACCAGGGCUUCCUUCUACCAGCUGUGGGCGGGCUUGGUCUGGUAACCUUGUCUGCUCUGCCAUUCCACUGCUCCUCCAUCCACUCGCCAAUCCCAAGAGUCUGGCCUCCCUCCAGCCCUGGGCAGACUGACCAGCAAGGUGGACCUUUACAUUCAAGCACAGCUGGCUUUUAUGACAUAAAGAACUAAAGGCCGAAAGAAUCUCUUGCUGCUGCAAAGAACAGAUUUUAUAUUUCUUCCUCUAAUCUUGGCAAAUGACCUUUACCUUUUGGAAAGAUUUCAUAUUGCUUCCUCCUCCCUGGAUAGGACCUAAUGUAGCACAGCGGGACUCAAAGAGGAGGACAUUUUCUCUUGCCAGUGCACUGGGCAGUGGGGCUGUCCUUCAACUGCUGCUGCCAAAAUUGGUUUUCUAAAAUUCUUCCAGUAGAGACUAAAAGAAGAUUCAAUUCCUGUAACCCAAGACUGAGUCUUAGGGCUCCAGUCUCCACCUGCUUGGUUUCCUAUCCUUUGCUGCCUGCCUGGGGUGGCCUGGAAGCCUGUUCAGAAAGGCACAAUGUGGAGCCUGGGGUGUCUCCCCCACCCCAGGACCGUCAGGUUUACCAGUGUGUGCAAUCGCCAUGUAUUCAGAGGGAAGUACCUUUGUUACCUACAACUUAGGAGCUAGGCCUCUGCUACAAGCACUUGAAAAUGAUAUUUUUAUUUUUAACGUCUCAACAAUCUGAUAUCGGAUGUCGUUUAACCUGGGCUCGUGGUAGGGCUCCAGCAUUUCUCCCUCCUUCCUGGUUUGCCUGUAGGGGUAGACUCGGAAGGUGGGUGGGGUGUGCAUUUCCUGUUAGGAGUGUAUCAGUGCUUGUCUUAUUAUAAGCCCCUUUCUUUUGUGAAUUUGAAGUAGCACCAACAAGCCUGGAUUGUGAAGGUAUUAAGAAUCGGUCUGUGGGCUACUGAGUGGGUCCUUAGGAUACUGGCCCAGAUUUUGCCACUGGGUAUGGCAGAUCAUUUUCUACCAUGGCCUGCUGCUCUUGUAGUGGACUUCCUGAGUCCAAUCCCACCUCCUGGUGUAGAAUUUACACUGCUGCACCUGAGGUCGAUGUUUCAAAGUAAGAUCAAGCCAGUGUUUUGAUCUGGGCUCUGAGCACAAGUCAGGAAACACCAACAUAUUCACACUCUCCCAGUAGGUUCCUCAGUCCGAUGGUGAAUGGCUAUUCGUAAAUGGCUGGUCUGGCUCUUUGGUGUUGGAGCCUUUCCAAUAGCCCCAUGAAAAGAAGCAUCACCCAAGGAUAUUGUAAAAAGGAUGUAACAAGGAGAUAGGGUAGACAUUGUACUCAGUGGGCCUUGGGGCCUAGCCCAGCUCUGAGCAGAGGACUGUGGCAUUCACUGUCCUUGAGUGUUUCACCUUCUUGGAUAACACACGGGCCUUCUCUUCUGGAUUUCAUCAGAGAUUACAGCCAGAUGGGGGCUGAAGACCAUCCUCUUGACCACAGAGGUGUGACUGUGGGAAUUCCUCCCAAUUUAUGGUUUCCCAGAAAAUCUUAGUUCCUUUUAUUUAUAGAAUGCAUGUCUUUUGUGUUAAGAAACCAAAGAGAAAUAAAGAGAACACUCCUAAUA